AUUCCAAAUUCGGGAACCACCAGAAAGGCUGGCCUCUCUUCAACAUGGGAUCUUCUGGACUUUUGAGCCUCCUGGUGCUAUUCGUCCUCUUAGCGAAUGUCCAGGGACCUGGUCUGACUGAUUGGUUAUUUCCCAGGAGAUGUCCCAAAAUCAGAGAAGAAUGUGAAUUCCAAGAAAGGGAUGUGUGUACAAAGGACAGACAAUGCCAGGACAACAAGAAGUGUUGUGUCUUCAGCUGCGGAAAAAAAUGUUUAGAUCUCAAACAAGAUGUAUGCGAAAUGCCAAAAGAAACUGGCCCCUGCCUGGCUUAUUUUCUUCAUUGGUGGUAUGACAAGAAAGAUAAUACUUGCUCCAUGUUUGUCUAUGGUGGCUGCCAGGGAAACAAUAACAACUUCCAAUCCAAAGCCAACUGCCUGAACACCUGCAAGAAUAAACAGCCGUGUCCCAAAAUCAAAGUGGAAUGCGAAGUGGAAGAAAUAGACCAGUGUACCAAACCCAGAGAUUGCCCAGAAAACAUGAAGUGUUGCCCGUUCAGCCGUGGAAAGAAAUGUUUAGACUUCAGAAAGGCCUCUCUGUCUACAUAAAUCCAGGAUGCCUUCCCUGACCACCUUAGACCGCCUACACUCUUUCUUCUCUGCCCAUAUUAUUGAGCUCUAAAGAAGAUCAUCAAGGACCAUUCGUUCAUUCUAUUCAUUCAACAAAUAUUGAUUGGUGCCCCUGACACCCAUGAUGGGUUCCACUUGCUCAUUGUGGCCAGGAAGGUCAGAAAAGUUUUUCUGGGAAAGAGAUCCAUGAUUUAAGAUCUGAAAGAUGAGUACUUAGACCAAAAAUGGGAAGAAAUAGCCUUUCAGGCCAGAUAAUAGGAUGUGCAAAGGCUCUGUGGCAGGAGGCAGGAUGUUCAGGUCUAGAAAGGCUAGAAAGCAGAGAGUGAGCAAGAGACAAGAAACAGGAAACUGGUAGUGUAUAUUCAGGGCAACUUGAAUCUGUAUUCCCAAGUGGCCAUCCUCAAGUUUUGGGGUCAAAUAAAUGCCCUACUUAAUGAUAUUUUCUGAAUCUUGUUACUUUAGGUUGACAUACCUUUCAAGACAAUAACUAGGUUUUCAGUGCUUUGAUAAAACCUCAAAUGUGUGGCCUUCCAGCCAGGCAUCUGUGGUUUCAUAUUGUUUAAGCAUUUGUUGCAUCCCUAUGGAUUGCAGCUCUCUAUAGGUUCGCUGUUGCUGAACCAAGAAAUAAGGCAUACACAGAUUUCUAGAGAAAUUGUAAUUCUAUAACAGAUUUUCAGGAGAUGAGGAAGGCUGGUAUCUUUCAGAGUACAAAGUGAUUUUGGAAUUGAAAGAAUUUCUUUGGGUUAAAGUUUGUCACUGACUUGUGUUCCUGAACCAUGAAGCAUGAAUAUGUGGGCUGAGAAAUAGUUUCUCUUGAUAAAUAAACAAGUAACAAAUUUUAAAAAGAGAGGAAGAUGAAGCUGGGCUAGUUGGGGGAAGGAGAGCUGGUAAGGGAUCUGGUCUUGAUCCUAACAGCAAUGGAUUAACCUAUGUUCAAAUCCCUUACCAUCUGUGUGGCCUCAAGAAAGUUAUUUAGCCUCUCUAAACCUUAGUUUUCUCAUCUGCAUAAUGAGAACAAUGAGAGGACCUACUUUACAAGAUUAAAUGUUAAUAGAUGUCAACUACUAAGAACACUAAUCAAUGCUAUAAUUGUUGUUUUGUUGUGCUGACACUAAUCAAUGCUACAAUUGUUGUUUUGUCGUGCUUCAGACCUGAGGUUCUAAAGAACUCUAUUUGUACCUCAUAGCACUAUGGGCAAAAUAAUUGCUCAAUAAAUGCUUAAGAUCAGGGUA